UAUAUAUUACCUUAUGCUUAGAACAAAUACUAUACAGUCUAAAGCCAACAGUUACUUACUGCUUAGCUGCUUCCCACUGGGGUAAGUCCUGUAGCCCUCAGAGGGGGCAGGCGGCCAUUGUCAUGUCAGAUCCCCAGUGAUGCGUGCUUGCAGGCUUGCCCCAACAAUGCUGGCAGUGACCUGUCUGUGCCCUUUCAGUCCUGACUCACAGGAUGGAGAUGGCCAAGAAGGGGACCCCUAUAAAAGACUUUAAGGAAAGGAGGGGGCACUUGAAAGGUAAUGCAUGUUCAUUGUAAAAAGAAAUCAGAAAAUAGAGCAAAGAUGAAGAAGAAAAUGAAAAUCAACCAUAUCCCAAUACUCAAAGAACUUUGUCAGCGAGCAAGAACAAUGCCAGGAGGUCUGGAGAAAACGUGUCAUCAGUGCAUUUCUAAAAUCGCCAGCAAUGCCUGCUUCGUUGUUGUGCUCUGUGCUUUCCUGGCUCUGCCGCUGUCCAUGACCUUCAUAGGAAUGAAAUUUUUGGAGGACUGCCCUAUACAGCCCCUCAUUCCUUUAUAUUUGCUAGUGGGUGGCAUCGUCGGUACCUUAAAGGGGAGACAAAACAACUUCCCCCUAAGCGUGGUUGCUGAAGUGAUGGGGCUAGCUCCAGAGACACAGAUUUUUCCAGAUGCAGGGCAUUUACCCAGGGCUGUGCAUAUUUGCAAGAGCUUCCUUCCUGCUGUUGAGUUCAAUGUGCUAAGCUGUGGCUUUGGUCUGACAAGAGUUGAUGCAGAGGAGUCCCUGACUGCCAGUUAUACCAUUGAAUUCAGCCAGUGAAAUCAUGGUCUUUCUCUGCGCUGCUGCUGCUGCUGCUUUUUUUUUUUUUGCUUUUUUUUUUUUUUUUUUUGAGGAAAAAAAAGCUUCCUGUUGAAGGCAGGGUUUGCAUUUGGUUAAAAUAUGUUUGAUUUAGCAGUUCCUAUUUCUGCUUUUAACUAUACUUCCUAGUUCUCAAUUGACUAACAUAGGAUUAAUUGGCUGCAGUUAUCAAUCAACUAUUAAAGUAUUCUUAUGCCUGAGGUAGGAGUGCUUCUCUGUGACUCUCAAGGUUAUGUAGUUAAUCUGCUCCUGGGCUGUAUUGACAUUUGUUUAAACAGAAAAAGCAACUGAAGAAGAAAUAUCAGGGGCGUGCAUAGCCUGCAAUUGUUUUCAAGAUCCCUGGCCCACAGAAAUGUUACACCUACCAAGAGAAGCUUAGGUCAGCCUCUGUCUAUCAACAACUCUUCCCAGUCUUCCAAGCCCACCUCACCACUUUCUAUAUCAAAGCCAGAAAACACAAGCAUCCAUUUUCCCAAGAUGGUUUCAUAAAAACAAAGCCGUAACACAAGAGAAAACUGAGUCAAGAGUGCCAAGUAUGAACUCUCAUUCGGACCCAGUGUUGGGUUUCUUUGCCAGCUGCCUUCUGGUGCGGGGAUCCUUGGAGAGAUCCUGGCCAGUGGCGCUGGUCAUGCUGUUGAUCUAAGACAUCAAAGGAACGUCUUGAAAAUUGCUGUUCUCAUAUGCAAUUGGUAGCCACAAGCUCAACUCUGUCGUGGGAGACGUCUGAUUUGGGGCAAACCUUAGGAGGCUUUUGUGUUUGAGGUAACCUCACUGUUAAAUGUCCCCAUCUCCUAACAGCAAUCUGGUGGGCAGUGUCCUAAAAUGUACAAGUACACACAAUCAUCCCCAUCACAACAUCCCCAUGGGAUCUACCUGGGACUCUGUUCAGCUCCAAGAAAACCCAAAGGCUCUUGGCUCAGCGGGGCCACAUUUUCCCCAUGGCCCCCACAGUGUUAAGGGAAGGCUCUAACGGUUUGAGUGCCAUAGAGAUGCUUAAAACAAGGGCAGCGUUUUCAGCAGUAAUUACCUCUGCCUCUCCUGUUCUCACUCAUCGUCAAGCUGCCCAGCAGAACUUUCCUUUAGAGAUGCUACUGUCCGUGGGGUCUGUUCCUCUUAAAAACAGCAAACUUUUCCUUUCUGAAAGCCAGCCCAGGACCCAAAGGUAAUUUAUUUUAGUGAACAAACUAAGGCCCUAAUAAGCAGCAUUGAUUUUUUGCCCUGGCAAUCUAAAACCGUUUGAAGCCAAAUUAAAUUUUUGUGCUCAUGAUGGCAAGGUAAUAUACAGUGAGUCCAUAACCAUUAGAGCAGCGGCAAACAGGAUUAGAGUCCCCAGAGGCAGAAGUUUGCCUGUGAUAAUGAUGGUUUGUAUUCAACCUCAGAACCUGCCUAGGGGGUCCCAACAUCCUUCGUGAAAUGCAUCAGAUAGCUUCACAGUAUUGCAUUCUAUGAAGAGAAACUUGAAGAGAUGUGAGCUGACAUUUCAUGGAGCUACCAGAAAGAACUGAGGGUCAUGCCCCAUUAAAAGAUCAGGAAAUGAAUUAAGUAGGCUGUGUGUGACCUGCUUUUUAAAAAAUAAAAUAGAAAAUUAGAGUGCCUAGUAAGUUAAGUAUUGUGUGAUACUUACAUAUGGACAUGUGUGUGUUUGGGUGAGUUGACCGUGUAAUUUAUCAUCCUAACUGGGACACUUUUGAGAGUACAAGGGGGCUCUAAUAAUCAUCCUGCCAGAGCAACAGCAUAAACCAGGACUUCUCUAAGCCAACAAGGACAUGCAGUUACCCAGUGACUAGGACCUGGCAUAAAAUGUAUUUGUUACUGAGGGUCAUGUUAAAAGACAGUUUCCAAAAGACGGAUUCAGUGACCAUUGCCUACCCUGCACUCCCCCUCAUCUUCCCACAUCACCCUUCCUAGUGGCAAUUGCUACCCCUAGUAAGCAUGUGCUUUUUGCUGAUGCCAUGCUGACGGCUCUGCCCUCAUUUGGAAUUCAUUCAGUCCUCACCGUGCCCCUUUGAGGCAGGUACUUGCUUCAGGAAGGAUUCUUUGACUACAAGGAACAAAAAAUCAACUCUGGCUAACUUAAGAGGUCAUUGAUUGGAAGAGCUCACAACCUCAAAGGUUAGUGGGAGAGAAGGGGGCCAGGUGGCUCCAGGAAGCCUGGGCAGUGGGACCCACUUGCCACGGCUCUUUCCUUGGGCUGGUUCCUUUCUCCUGGCAUCAUUGUAGCCAAGAACCAGUCCUGGGAGGGCAGCCAGAUCUGGGGACACGUGGUGGGUGGGGGAAUUCCUCCAAGGAAUGGGGCCCUGCAAGGAAGGGAAAUGCAUCUGAGUGAUGGAAACUUGAGCUGGACUCUCAGUUCCAGCUUACAGUGAGGAAACAGCGAGCUGGUGUUCAGCCUGGGCUUUCCCAACCACACAGCCACCGUCAGCCAACCUACUACAGGCAAUUGGUUUUUCCCCUACCCUAAACCCACCACCCUUCACCUUUGCCACACCACUCCCCCUCAGAGGAGGACCCUCGCACCUCUCCUUGUGCAUAGGGGUCCCAAGUAUGCCCCUUCUUCCAGGCAGCCCUCCCUGGAUGAGUCAGCUCUACUGUGGGUGGCUCUCUGAACUCCCCCAAGGCCUCACUUUCCUUUUCUUAUGGAGAUGUUCUGCCUCCCAGCCGGGCUGCAAGUCUUAGGCGAGAACCCUCCAAUUUAAUUUCCUCCGAUUUAAUCAUCAGUGUACUGUGGUGUAGACAGUGGUCAAAGAGGUGUGGACCACUGCCCUUCUCAUUCUCUUACUCACUGUGGAUCUCAGUGAAGUGACUUAACUUCUCUGAGCCUUAGUUUCCUCAUUUGGGCAACAGAGAUAAUACGCGGCCCCAGGCUAGGAUGGACAUUAAAGAUCACACAUACCAAGCAUUAAACUAACCACUCUCCUUAGGUUUUGUAUCUUUACAUAAGUAAUAACUCUCCAUUUUGGAAAAUCAGAGAAUGCAGAUAAGCACAAAGAAGAAAAUCAAAAUCAUCUGUAAAUUUCACCACCCAGAGAAAAUUGCUGUUGACAUUUUGGCCCAAUGGCUCCAGUUUUGGUCCUGCGCCCAUGUUUAUUUAGUACCUCUAGCCUCAGGCUGGGAGAAUUCAUUGAGAUAAUGUAUGUCAAGCGCUUUGCCCAGCACCAGGGUCUAUUUUUGUACAACAUCCAUUCCCAGAGUCACUAUCACCUCCUCACGGGUAACCCCCAGAUCUCUGCCAGGAGUCCUCACCUCUCUCUGUUCACCUCCAGGCUCUGACUCUGCCCCCUGUGGGCCACUAGACCCUGCAUUUCCAUCCAAAAUUUUAAAUGGAACAAGUCCAAAUCUGGAGUUAUCACCUACCCAAGGCACAGCUUGGGGUUCGCUGUUCCCAUCUCUCUGUCUCUCUUUAUUUUAUCCUUGCUUCUCUUUACAGUUUGGAGCCCAGUUAGCUGCAUCUCUUGGCUCCUGCUUGCCCUUCCAUUUCACUCAAGCUCAGCAUCUCUCCCCGCCUCUGCCAGUCGGCCACAUCCUCCGUCAUCCAAGGAUUCUUUCUAAUGCCCUGCUCUCCAGGGUUAGGGGUGCCAUGAGUGUGGCCUCGGGAGAGAUGGGUAGCCUAGGAAGCCAGAGAGAGCAGAUACACAGGUCAGGCUUUCAAAAACAUCACAGAUCAAGUUGCUAGGUAGAGAAGACGGGGAGCUGUUAAGGCAUUCCUUAGCAAAGACCACCUGUGUCCUUCCACCGCUGCAUUUCCAGGGGGAAAGUGUGCUCCCCUGUGACAAAGGCAUUUGUGGCCAGUUAGAGUCGGGUGGGUCGUGGUGCUUUGUGUAACCAAGUGGCAGCAGAAUUUCGAAGGCGUGUCAGGCUGGAGUCAGGGACCAUCUACCAGGGGCCCAGAUGGUCUGUCCCCCAAGAGUAUCACUCCCAGGACAAGGGUCUGUGCUCUUGACUUGAAAGAUGUACGAGGACUGAGAGGGACUCUCAGUCCACAGCCCCACUUGGGAAUUCCAGAUGCCUGAGAUGGGCAGUGGUACAAACUUCCAAGAAGAGAGAAAGCAGGCUGGGCGGGGCUGGGGUGGGGAGGAAACGGCUCACGGUACCUGGAUUCGGCCAAGCCUGUUACAUGGCCUGGAAGUACCAGGGAAAAGUCUGCUAGGGGUUCCUCCCAAGACAGAGGGAUAUAUUUCAAGGUCCUCUAGCAUGCGGACCAGGUGUCAUUUUUACAUUAUGUGUGGGUGCAAAUGUGCUAGCACAAUACAGGAGAGAGUCAGUCUGAACCUUGAUGCAGAGAUGGGUUACCCCAGCCAAUCCCUUGUCCAAACCAACUCACACAUCUAAAAGGAAAACACCACUGAGGAUGCUGGCGAUGAAUUUAUGCCUUCAUUCUUGCCAGUUUUAAUUCUUAUUCUUCAAAUUAAAUUUCGUUGCUUGAUGGCAUUUGUAACUCCAGUGUGUUGUUCACUUUUCAUAACACCUUCCUCUCUCUCCUCUUUCUCUCUCCCUGCCAACACCCCACCACCGCUACCUUCUAUCCCCUCUCUUCCCGUCUAUUUUGCUGCUCUGCCUUGCCACCCUGGCUCCCCACCACGCCCCAGGUGUCUCUCCUGUUGUACGACUCCACCAGGAUGAGGCGGCUGCUGUCCAAGGCCGUGGUGAUUGAUGACGAUGACGAUGACGAAUACCCCUGGAGGCAGAAUGCGCACAGAUACUACAUCCACCUCCUGCUGAGCCUCUUCCUCUUCCUCUGGUUCAUCCUGGGAAACUACUGGGUCUUUUCUGUGUACCUGCCUGAUUUUCUUCCCCCUUUCCAGCAGCCUCAGGACUACUGUGACAAAACCCUGUACCUCUUUGCAGUCGGAGUCCUGGCGCUCAGUCACACUGUGCUGGUCUUGCUCCUGCUGUGCAGCGGCUGUGUCUACCUGUGCUCCAGGUGGAGACUUGCUGCCGAUGAAGACUGACAGCUGCCUUGUCCAGCAUACCAUGUAUGCAUAUGCGUGUGCAUGCACGCGCGUGCACACAGACACACAGACGCACACACACACACACACACACACAGGUUCAGAGAAGGGCAUAAAGGUAAUAAAACCUUCCCUGAAGGCAUUUAAAAAGCCACCCAAAGGCACUGAAUAUAAUAGCAGACUAAAGAAACUCUUGCCUUCCUAGACAUGGGGAAAUCACUUCUGCUCUUUUCAGAGUGGGAAUUUUGUUCUCACAAGAGUUUUCAAAGGGAUAAUUGUUUUUGAGGGUAUGAAGUGUGGGAGGCAAAGAAUGGGAGACCUUUUCAAAUCAUAGUGCAAUUUCAAUGACUGGUGCAAGAGCAAGGUUGGUUGUUGCUACUGCUGCUGUCAUUCAGCCAUGGUCACCUUGAAGUUAUAGAAAGUGCACAGACUUUCACACAAGAUAUAUCUUAACUUCACUCGCUAUGAUGGCUUUUGUUAUUAAAAGGAAAAAGAUAUUCUUUUAGUGACUCUAGCUGCCUUUUGGGAAAGUGAAGGAGCAGUCUCUUCCAGCCCUAUAUCAGAUAGGUUUGACGUGAUGGGUGGAACAUCCCAAGGUCAGCUAUAAAAUCUAACAACGUCAAAGCAGUAGCUUCCACAUAGGGGGCGGGCUGGCCUGCUACAGGCAUUGCGGAGUGCAGCGCCGUGUGCACCGUGUGCCGCUGCUGCAGGUUCUUUGCUUGGCCUUGAGUCUGUCUCUGCCUCUGGCUAUUCAAGUACCUCUCUAUGAUCUGCGGCUGGCUGGGUGGCAUAAACCAGUUUUGUAUGUUUCUGGACAGGUUGCAUGAGUUGGGGUGCCGUCAGUGUAGCUGUUUUUGGUUUCUGAGCUUAAAUAUCGAAUAAUAGCUCCUCAACCUAAUGACCAGUUAGGCUUUGGAAGCCUUUUGUAAAUUGAGAUGUCUGGAAGUCCAGGAUGACACCGAACAGUGACCACUAACCUUCCCUCUGGCUGCCGCUGUUGAGAGAUGAAGUCCAGGUCUGUUGUCAGUGCUCGCUGGGGAGCCUCUUUAUGAGCAAAAAGUCCCAUGUUUUAGAAUUUUGUAUGAAGAUACUGUCAUGAGUGUUUCUAGGGCAGUGCCCAGGGGUGCGUGGCACCUGCUUAACCGUGCUUCUCUCAGCCACGUGCAUAGCAUUUCUGUAUAUUUACACACUGCUGAGCUGUGUUUAUUUUUUAACUUUGUUAUGUUUUCGUGCUUUCUCAUCAAACCAAUCCCUGAGUGGCCAUGAAUGGAGGCACCUCCCUUCAUCAGAAGUGUCAGCUCAAACCAAGAGGCUCAUUCUUCUCCGUAGCUUUAAGAGAAAGGCCCCGUGAGUCCCAUGGGGUCUUCCCAUUUCAGUUUAGAAGCACUCCCCGGGCAGUCACCGUUAGUCCCCCUUUCCUCCCAGGUGAGAAGAAAGUGCUUGGUGUGCCAUCUGCUGGACAAAGGAAGAACAGCCCUUUUUUUGCCCCUGUCCCUAAGGGCAGUUUCUGUUUUCAUUUUCACUUGAGCCAUGGCAGAAGACCAGCGGGUGUGCAGUUUGCAGAUCCUACCUCACCUAUGAUGCCCAAUUCCAUCCUCACUGUGUCCCACGUUGCCCUCUCUGUGUUGGGGACUGGGGAGAGUCUGUGGGCUAUGAUACUGGGGUGGACAGGAGUUCCAUGGGCUCCUCUCCCACCCUCCUUUCCCCAGUCCAUGACUCGUCAGCCAUUCCCAGUCACUUAGCCAAUGCUUGGACAUCUGUGAGCAGCAAAGACCUGGGCCCAGGGACACCUGCAUGACUCCCACAUGAAAGCCUCUGAGGCUUCUGUUGCGAGGGCCUUGGCAAAGGCGGAAAGAGCUGUGAACAACCAUGGGCAUGAAGAUUUCUGUUAGCAGAUGGCAGGUACUGGUUAGUGCUUUGGAUACAUCAGUAGCUAGGUCUCAAACGUUGGACAUUCCCAGUUUCUGGUAGGCAUGAGUAUCACCAGAGUGUUGCAGAAAUCUUUCCCAGAGGGAGUGGUGGAUGAAGUGUGCUCAUUCUCAUAUGCACCCCACCAGCCCACCCCCAGUUGCAAUGGAGAAUACUGGUCAUAGGUCCUAAAUAAUUGCUAAAAUCUGGACUAUAUUUUUAGCUUUGAGUUUUCUUGUCACCAAAGCAGUAAGGAAGAGGUGAUGAUCUCUUUGUAUAGGUCAUACAUCUUCCCUGGUUUGAGGUUACAGUGAGCUAUGAUUGCACCACUGCACUCUACUCUGGGUGACAGAAUGAGACCCCAUCUCUAAAAAACAAAAUUACCCCCUUCUGGGGAAACAGGUUAGAUCCUAAAGAAAAUGUUCAUGUGCAUCCAUUCAUAGAGGGGACACUGAAUGGUUCAGUGGGUGACAUCUUCAAGCGCAGCAGGCUUUGAAUGAUAACUGAUUAAGGCCUCCCUCAGGAGAUGGUGAGAUGGUUAUGAUAAGGCACAUUUCAAGAAAGAGGCUCUGGGGCUAAGUAAGGCAAAUGGUCUAUAACUGUGGUUCUUUGAAGUCUGGCUUAAUCCAGGGAUGACACCCAGACUGUCUAGGAAGGGCUGAGCUGCGUGCCCUUUAAGUGAUCACCUCUUAGUAUAAUUUCACUGAGCUGGAGGUGAGUGUAAGAAGUUCCUGGUUAUAGAAGAAGUUAUAAUCCUUGGCAUGGCCUGAAGUAGGCAGUCCACACUGAUAUGAAAUGUGCUGUGUAUACCUGGAGAAUGAAAAUGCCCAUCUAAGACUGGCCCAAGAGCUGGGCAGCCUUCCUCCAUGGGAACCUGGCAAGGCAAUGGGAAGUGGACAUGGGAACACCUGAACUUUCUGGAUGCUAUGAAACCUCAAGGGAACAAAUUAUGUGGCAGAGAGGGAUAAUCUGUUCUUCCCAUCUGAGAAAAGACUGCAGCAAAGAUAAACUAUAUGUUGAGAUCAUUUUAUUUGCUACAUCGGGCAUCAUUCUAAAAACCAUUCUUUGCCUGAAUCUAUAUAAAUGACAGUUGAAAGCAGUAAAAGUGGGACUGUUUCACUGGAGUCAGCCACACUAGUGGUUCUCAAAUCUUGGUGAACCCUGAGAGCUACCCAAGGACUUGUUUGCAAUGCAGAAUCACAGCCCCCAGAGACUGACUUGUGGGGCCCAGCUGGUUCUGAUUCGGUGGCCAGAGAAACCGCAUGUGUGCACUCGGGCCACACAUACAGCCUGGACUGGCUUAUGUCAGGCCCAUCCUGGUUGUCACCAUGAGGACAAUAUAAUGUCACUUCCAGUACUUCGUGUUAUUUCCUUCUCUUUUAGUAUGAGAAGUGGCCAAGUGGUCAAUAGCUUUCAUCUUUGUGUAACUGAAUCUUGUGCUUCAUUUCCUUCUGGGCAUUUUUCAUUGUUGAUGAAAUAAACUUUGUUCAAUUUGU